UUUCUUUUUCUUUUUUUUAUCUGGAGACUGAGUUUUGCACUCGUUGCCCAGGCUGGAGUGCAAUGGUGCGAUCUCAGCUCACUGCAGUCUCCACCUCAGCAGGAGAGCAGGAAUCUUCAGUGAUCCACGGGCAGAUCUGCAGCCAUUGUGGGCACCUGUUCCUCCCGCGACCUUUGUGCCCACGUCUCUCCCUCCAGUACCUAUUGCACGACCCCCCCCACGUCCGCCUCCUGCCAUUGCCAGCAAGUGCCUUGCGCGGGUACCUGGCUGCGCUUAUUAAUCCAUUAUGGUCGCUCUGUCACUGGUGCCAUUAUGUGCUCACAUGCCCACUCCCUCAGGUUUAGAAGUCGCGUCGCCCGGCAACAGAACAAUCUGCUGGCUUAGCCUUUGGCCAAGUUGGCAGCUGGACGAGGACGCUCAGAGCCCAGCUCUCGAGAGUUCAAGUAUCCGACAGUUCCCCACUGCUCCCAGGAGCGGUUACCCGGGCACUCUGUGCCCCUCAUUCCUGUUUGGGCCAAGGCCGAGGACCUGCGAGUAGGGCUCAGUUGCCUAGAGCCCCUUCAGCCCAUCGCCCAGUUCACUUUGCUUGUGGGAUCUCCCCGUUGCUCCUGCCCCUGGACUGAGUGGCAGGCCAUCCUACAAACACCCGGACACUCAACAUCAGUGGUGUCAAGACAACUCUAAGAAGGUUUUCCGUGAUCCUGCAAGACCUGUGUUCCAUCCUGGUGAUUCUGUCUCCAAUUUCACUGCACAGGUACCACAGUAAGCCAGUGCUGUGUGCUCCGAAUUCCAGGGCAUCCCCCAGCUCAGCCACUACACUGAGCACAAGGACUCUGUGGGGCCCAGGAGCAGGUAGUCACCCCUUUGGGGUCCUCAACACCCGGCUGUCCCCAGACUUGUGUCCAGGGAAGAUAGUGUUGAGGGCCCUCAAGGAGAGCAGGGCAGGGAUGCCUGAGCAGGACAAGGACCCCAGAGUCCAAGAAAAUCCUGCUGAUCAGAGAACGGUCCCCGAGGUCACCGGGGAUGCACGGUCUGCAUUUUGGCCCCUGCGGGACAAUGGAGGCCUCUCUCCCUUUGUGCCCAGGCCCGGGCCUCUGCAGACAGACCUCGAUGCCCAGAGCUCAGAAAUCAGAUAUAACCAGACAUCCCAGACAUCCUGGACGAGCUCGAGCACAAAACGAAAUGCCAUCUCCAGCUCCUACAGCUCCACGGGAGGCUUGCCGGGGCUAAAGCAGAGGAGGGGACCAGCCUCAUCCCGCUGCCAGCUGACCCUCAGUUACUCAAAGACAGUGAGUGAGGACAGGCCUCAGGCUGUCUCUUCGGGUCACACACGGUGUGAAAAGGCGGCAGAUACAGCACCAGGGGAGACACUCGCCCCAAGGGGUGGCUCCCCCAGAUCCCAGGCCUCUAGGCCCCGUAGACGCAAGAUUCGCCUGCUGCCAAGCAGGCGAGGGGAGCCUUUGAUGCUGCCACCUCCCUUAGAGCUGGGGUACCGGGUCACGGCGGAAGACCUGCACCUGGAAAAACAGGCAGCAUUCCAGCGCAUCAACAGUGCACUGCACGUUGAGGACAAGGCCAUCUCGGACUGCAGACCCUCACGGCCUUCCCACACUUUGUCCUCACUUGCAACAGGGGCUUCGGGUGGGCCUCCCCUUUCUAAAGCACCCACUAUGGAUGCACAGCAGGACAGACCCAAGUCCCAAGACUGCCUGGGCCUAGUGGCCCCCCUAGCAUCUGCUGCAGAGGUCUCCUCUACAGCUCCCGUGUCUGGGAAGAAGCAGAGACCACCAGGACCCCUGUUCUCCUCCUCAGAUACCCUUCCUGCCACCUCUUCCCACUCCCGGGACUCAGCCCAGGUCACCUCGAUGAUUCCUGCCCCCUUCACAGCUGCAAGCAGGGAUGCCGGCAUGAGAAGAACAAGGUCGGCCCCUGCAGCUGCCGCAGCAGCCCCUCCCCCCUCCACAUUGAACCCCACGUCGGGGUCACUACUCAAUGCAGUGGAUGGAGGCCCCUCACAUUUCUUGGCCUCAGCCACAGCUGCAGCACGUGCCCAGAGGUCAGAAGUGAGAUAUAACCAGAGAUCCCAGACCACCCGGACCAGAUCCUGCCUCAAACGAAAUGCCAGCUCCAGCUCCCACAGCUCUACGGAAGGCCUCCCGGAACUAAAGCGGAGGAGGGGGCCAGCCUCAUCCCACUGCCAGCUGGCCCACAGUUCCUCAAAGACAGUGAGUGAGGACGGAGCUCAGGCUGUCUCUACGGGUCACCGCUGUGAAAAGAAGGCAGACACAGCACCAGGGCAGACACUCGCCCCCAGGGGUGGCUCCCCCAGAUCCCAGGCCUCUAGGCCCCACAUCAACAGUGCACUGCACGUUGAGGACAAGGCCAUCUCGGACUGCAGACCCUCACGGCCUUCCCACACUUUGUCCUCACUUGCAACAGGGGCUUCGCGUGGGCCUCCCGUUUCUAAAGCACCCACUAUGGAUGCACAGCAGGACAGACCCAAGUCCCAAGACUGCCUGGGCCUAGUGGCCCCCCUAGCAUCUGCUGCAGAGGUCCCCUCUACAGCUCCCGUGUCUGGGAAGAAGCACAGACCACCAGGACCCCUGUUCUCCUCCUCAGAUACCCUUCCUGCCACCUCUUCCCACUCCCGGGACUCAGCCCAGGUCACCUCGAUGAUUCCUGCCCCCUUCACAGCUGCAAGCAGGGAUGCCGGCAUGAGAAGAACAAGGUCGGCUCCUGCAGCUGCCGCAGCAGCCCCUCCCCCCUCCACAUUGAACCCCACGUCGGGGUCACUACUCAAUGCAGUGGAUGGAGGCCCCUCACAUUUCUUGGCCUCAGCCACAGCUGCAGCACGUGCCCAGAGGUCAGAAGUGAGAUAUAACCAGAGAUCCCAGACCUCCCGGACCAGAUCCUGCCUCAAACGAAAUGCCAGCUCCAGCUCCCACAGCUCUACGGAAGGCCUCCCGGAACUAAAGCGGAGGAGGGGGCCAGCCUCAUCCCACUGCCAGCUGGCCCACAGUUCCUCAAAGACAGUGAGUGAGGACGGAGCUCAGGCUGUCUCUACGGGUCACCGCUGUGAAAAGAAGGCAGAUACAGCACCAGGGCAGACACUCGCCCCCAGGGGUGGCUCCCCCAGAUCCCAGGCCUCUAGGCCCCACAUCAACAGUGCACUGCACGUUGAGGACAAGGCCAUCUCGGACUGCAGACCCUCACGGCCUUCCCACACUUUGUCCUCACUUGCAACGGGGGCUUCGGGUGGGCCUCCCGUUUCUAAAGCACCCGCUAUGGAUGCACAGCAGGACAGACCCAAGUCCCAAGACUGCCUGGGCCUAGUGGCCCCCCUAGCAUCUGCUGCAGAGGUCUCCUCUACAGCUCCCGUGUCUGGGAAGAAGCACAGACCACCAGGACCCCUGUUCUCCUCCUCAGAUCCCCUUCCUGCCACCUCUUCCCACUCCCGGGACUCAGCCCAGGUCACCUCGCUGAUUCCUGCCCCCUUCACAGCUGCAAGCAGGGAUGCCAGCAUGAGAAGAACAAGGCCUGGCACCUCCGCUCCUGCAGCUGCAGCAGCAGCCCCUCCCCCCUCCACAUUGAACCCCACGUCGGGGUCACUACUCAAUGCAGUGAAUGGAGGCCCCUCACAUUUCUUGGCCUCAGCCACAGCUGCAGCACGUGCCCAGAGGUCAGAAGUGAGAUAUAACCAGAGAUCCCAGACCUCCCGGACCAGAUCCUGCCUCCAAGGAAAUGCCAGCUCCAGCUCCCACAGUUCUACGGAAGGCCUCCCGGAACUAAAGCGGAGGAGGGGGCCAGCCUCAUGCCACUGCCAGCUGGCCCUCAGUUCCUCAAACACAGUGAGUGAGGACGGACCUCAGGCUGUCUCUUCGGGUCACACCCGCUGUCAAAAGGCAGAUACAGCACCAGGGCAGACACUCGCCCCCAGGGGUGGCUCCCCCAGAUCCCAGGCCUCUAGGCCCCACAUCAACAGUGCACUGCACGUUGAGGGCAAGGCCAUCUCGGACUGCAGACCCUCACGGCCUUCCCACACUUUGUCCUCACUUGCAACGGGGGCUUCGCGUGGGCCUCCCCUUUCUAAAGCACCCACUAUGGAUGCACAGCAGGACAGACCCAAGUCCCAAGACUGCCUAGGCCUAGUGGCCCCCCUAGCAUCUGCUGCAGAGGUCUCCUCUACAGCUCCCGUGUCUGGGAAGAAGCACAGACCACCAGGACCCCUGUUCUCCUCCUCAGAUCCCCUUCCUGCCACCUCUUCCCACUCCGGGGACUCAGCCCAGGACACCUCGCUGAUUCCUGCCCCCCUCACACCUGCAAGCAGGGAUGCCGGCGUGAGAAGAAUGUUUUGUGUUCGAAAUUGUUUGAGGGGUUUGGGUUUAUUUUUGUUGGUUUUUUCUUUUUUGUUUUUGCUUACAUGGGCAUCCUUCAGCUUUUAAUAAUCUGAAAAGCUCUA